AGCUGAAAAAGCUGGAGCAACCAAGCAGGGCCUACAAGCCGAGGAGGGCUGUUUAAAGGCGCAGGGGCCAUUUUACCUCCAGGUUGGCCCUGCUCAGGACCAGGAGGAAACACCUCCAGCCCGCGACCUCCUCCCACAGGGGGAAAAGGAAAGCAGGAGGACCACAGAAGCUUUGGCACCGAGGAUCCCCGCAGUCUUCACCCGCGGAGAUUCCGGCUGAAGGAGCUGUCCAGCGACUACACCGCUAAGCGCAGGGAGCCCAAGCCUCCGCACCGGAUUCCGGAGCACAAGCUCCACCGCGCAUGCGCACACGCCCCAGACCCAGGCUCAGGAGGACUGAGAAUUUUCUGACCGCAGUGCACCAUGGGAAGCUCUGAAGUUUCCAUAAUUCCUGGGCUCCAGAAAGAAGAAAAGGCGGCCGUGGAGAGACGAAGACUUCAUGUGCUGAAAGCUCUGAAGAAGCUAAGGAUUGAGGCUGAUGAGGCCCCAGUUGUUGCUGUGCUGGGCUCAGGCGGAGGACUGCGGGCUCACAUUGCCUGCCUUGGGGUCCUGAGUGAGAUGAAAGAACAGGGCCUGUUGGAUGCCGUCACGUACCUCGCAGGGGUCUCUGGAUCCACUUGGGCAAUAUCUUCUCUCUACACCAAUGAUGGUGACAUGGAAGCUCUCGAGGCUGACCUGAAACAUCGAUUUACCCGACAGGAGUGGGACUUGGCUAAGAGCCUACAGAAAACCAUCCAAGCAGCGAGGUCUGAGAAUUACUCUCUGACCGACUUCUGGGCCUACAUGGUUAUCUCUAAGCAAACCAGAGAACUGCCGGAGUCUCAUUUGUCCAAUAUGAAGAAGCCCGUGGAAGAAGGGACACUACCCUACCCAAUAUUUGCAGCCAUUGACAAUGACCUGCAACCUUCCUGGCAGGAGGCAAGAGCACCAGAGACCUGGUUCGAGUUCACCCCUCACCACGCUGGCUUCUCUGCACUGGGGGCCUUUGUUUCCAUAACCCACUUCGGAAGCAAAUUCAAGAAGGGAAGACUGGUCAGAACUCACCCUGAGAGAGACCUGACUUUCCUGAGAGGUUUAUGGGGAAGUGCUCUUGGUAACACUGAAGUCAUUAGGGAAUACAUUUUUGACCAGUUAAGGAAUCUGACCCUGAAAGGUUUAUGGAGAAGGGCUGUUGCUAAUGCUAAAAGCAUUGGACACCUUAUUUUUGCCCGAUUACUGAGGCUGCAAGAAAGUUCACAAGGGGAACAUCCUCCCCCAGAAGAUGAAGGCGGUGAGCCUGAACACACCUGGCUGACUGAGAUGCUCGAGAAUUGGACCAGGACCUCCCUGGAAAAGCAGGAGCAGCCCCAUGAGGACCCCGAAAGGAAAGGCUCACUCAGUAACUUGAUGGAUUUUGUGAAGAAAACAGGCAUUUGCGCUUCAAAGUGGGAAUGGGGGACCACUCACAACUUCCUGUACAAACACGGUGGCAUCCGGGACAAGAUAAUGAGCAGCCGGAAGCACCUCCACCUGGUGGAUGCUGGUUUAGCCAUCAACACUCCCUUCCCACUCGUGCUGCCCCCGACGCGGGAGGUUCACCUCAUCCUCUCCUUCGACUUCAGUGCCGGAGAUCCUUUCGAGACCAUCCGGGCUACCACUGACUACUGCCGCCGCCACAAGAUCCCCUUUCCCCAAGUAGAAGAGGCUGAGCUGGAUUUGUGGUCCAAGGCCCCCGCCAGCUGCUACAUCCUGAAAGGAGAAACUGGACCAGUGGUGAUGCAUUUUCCCCUGUUCAACAUAGAUGCCUGUGGAGGUGAUAUUGAGGCAUGGAGUGACACAUACGACACAUUCAAGCUUGCUGACACCUACACUCUAGAUGUGGUGGUGCUACUCUUGGCAUUAGCCAAGAAGAAUGUCAGGGAAAACAAGAAGAAGAUCCUUAGAGAGUUGAUGAACGUGGCCGGGUAGGUGGGAGACCAUAGUCGCUCUGAUGCCUAUGCUCGUUCAGCUCUACUACCCGAAGGAUAGUGCCCGAAGUUGCUGCUUGGCAUAGAUGAGCCUCAGCUUCCAGGGCACUGUGGGCCUGUUGGUCUACUAGGGCCCUGAUGUCCACCUGGCCUUCCUGUUCUUCACUCCCUUCAGCCACACGCUUCAUGGCCUUGAGUUCACCUUGGCUGUCCUAACAGGGCCAAUCACCAGUGACCAGCUAGACUGUGAUUUUGAUAGCGUCAUUCAGAAGAAGGCGUCCAAGGAGCUGAAGGUGGUGAAAUUUGUCCUGCAGGUCCCUCGGGAGAUCCUGGAGCUGGAGCAUGAGUGUCUGACAAUCAGAAGCAUCAUGUCCAAUGUCCAGAUGGCCAGAAUGAAUGUGAUAGUUCAGACCAAUGCCUUCCACUGCUCCUUUAUGACUGCACUUCUAGCCAGUAGCUCUGCACAAGUUAGCUCUGUAGAAGUAAGAACUUGGGCUUAAAUCAUGGGCUAUCUCUCCACAGCCAAGUGGAGCUCUGAGAAUACAACAAGUGCUCAAUAAAUGCUUGCUGAUUGACUGAUGGA